GGUACACUGUUGGAGAGAUGAGACAGUCACACCAGCUGCCCCUAGUGGGGCUCUUACUGUUUUCUUUUAUUCCAAGCCAACUAUGCGAGAUUUGUGAGGUAAGUGAAGAAAACUACAUCCGCCUAAAACCUCUGUUGAAUACAAUGAUCCAGUCAAACUAUAACAGGGGAACCAGCGCUGUCAAUGUUGUGUUGUCCCUCAAACUUGUUGGAAUCCAGAUCCAAACCCUGAUGCAAAAGAUGAUCCAACAAAUCAAAUACAAUGUGAAAAGCAGAUUGUCAGAUGUAAGCUCGGGAGAGCUUGCCUUGAUUAUACUGGCUUUGGGAGUAUGUCGUAACGCUGAGGAAAACUUAAUAUAUGAUUACCACCUGAUCGACAAGCUAGAAAAUAAAUUCCAAGCAGAAAUUGAAAAUAUGGAAGCACACAAUGGCACUCCCCUGACUAACUACUACCAGCUCAGCCUGGACGUUUUGGCCUUGUGUCUGUUCAAUGGGAACUACUCAACCGCCGAAGUUGUCAACCACUUCACUCCUGAAAAUAAAAACUAUUAUUUUGGUAGCCAGUUCUCAGUAGAUACUGGUGCAAUGGCUGUCCUGGCUCUGACCUGUGUGAAGAAGAGUCUAAUAAAUGGGCAGAUCAAAGCAGAUGAAGGCAGUUUAAAGAACAUCAGUAUUUAUACAAAGUCACUGGUAGAAAAGAUUCUGUCUGAGAAAAAAGAAAAUGGUCUCAUUGGAAACACAUUUAGCACAGGAGAAGCCAUGCAGGCCCUCUUUGUAUCAUCAGACUAUUAUAAUGAAAAUGACUGGAAUUGCCAACAAACUCUGAAUACAGUGCUCACGGAAAUUUCUCAAGGAGCAUUCAGCAAUCCAAACGCUGCAGCCCAGGUCUUACCUGCCCUGAUGGGAAAGACCUUCUUGGAUAUUAACAAAGACUCUUCUUGCGUCUCUGCUUCAGGUAACUUCAACAUCUCCGCUGAUGAGCCUAUAACUGUGACACCUCCUGACUCACAAUCAUAUAUCUCCGUCAAUUACUCUGUGAGAAUCAAUGAAACAUAUUUCACCAAUGUCACUGUGCUAAAUGGUUCUGUCUUCCUCAGUGUGAUGGAGAAAGCCCAGAAAAUGAAUGAUACUAUAUUUGGUUUCACAAUGGAGGAGCGCUCAUGGGGGCCCUAUAUCACCUGUAUUCAGGGCCUAUGUGCCAACAAUAAUGACAGAACCUACUGGGAACUUCUGAGUGGAGGCGAACCACUGAGCCAAGGAGCUGGUAGUUACGUUGUCCGCAAUGGAGAAAACUUGGAGGUUCGCUGGAGCAAAUACUAAUAAGCCCAAACUUUCCUCAGCUGCAUAAAAUCCAUUUGCAGUGGAGUUCCAUGUUUAUUGUCCUUAUGCCUUCUUCUUCAUUUAUCCCAGUACGAGCAGGAGAGUUAAUAACCUCCCCUUCUCUCUCUACAUGUUCAAUAAAAGUUGUUGAAAGAUUAACAACUAUA